ACCCUUCCCCCUUCUCCAACCGCCAACGGCCGCCUGCGCCUGAGGCCCGGCCCACGCCCCAUCCCGCUCGCUCCACGCUGCGGCAGCCCCGGCGGCCCCAGGUGCGCGGCCCCCGCCAUCCCGCCCCGCCGCCCUGCGCCAUGGAGGAGGGCCCUCUGCCGGGCGGGCUGCCCAGCCCCGAGGAUGCGAUGGUGACGGAGCUCUUAAGCCCCGAGGGUCCGUUCGCUUCGGAGAACAUCGGCCUGAAGGCCCCCGUGAAGUACGAGGAGGACGAGUUCCACGUCUUCAAAGAAGCGUACCUGGGCCCGGCGGACCCCAAGGAACCCGUCCUGCACGCGUUCAACCCCGCGCUGGGCGCCGACUGCAAGGGCCAGGUCAAGGCGAAGCUCGCGGGGGGCGACAGCGACGGCGGGGAGCUCCUCGGGGAGUACCCCGGGAUCCCAGAGCUCAGCGCGCUGGAGGACGUCGCGCUCCUGCAGGCCCCGCAGCCGCCCGCCUGCAACGUGCACUUCCUGUCCUCGCUGCUACCCGCGCACCGCAGCCCGGCGGUGUUGCCCCUGGGCGCCUGGGUCCUGGAAGGAGCCUCCCACCCGGGCGUCCGCAUGAUCCCAGUUGAAAUCAAGGAAGCAGGUGGUACUACUACAAGUAAUAAUCCGGAAGAAGCAACUUUGCAGAAUCUUCUUGCUCAGGAAUCCUGUUGCAAGUUCCCAUCGUCCCAGGAACUAGAGGAUGCCUCCUGCUGUUCUCUUAAGAAAGAUUCCAACCCAAUGCUUGAGGGAGCCUUACCAUCGGUAGUCAACGGGUCUGCUUUCCCCUCGGGAUCAACUCUUCCAGGACCACCAAAAAUAACUUUGGCUGGGAAAUGCACUUAAAGCUGUAAAUUACCCCUAUGGACUACUUUACUGCAUCCUACAAGAGUUGAUAUGCAGUACUUUCACUAUCAUCCGCUUGAAAUAGCUUGUCGUUUUUAUUGUAAUGUUCUCUUUACCUCAUGAGUUAUUUAGAUGUACAUUUCAUAGUGUCCACAUUUGUAUUAUAUAUACAUAUAUGUGUAUGUAUAUGUAUAUAUUUUUAAAUGAUAUUUUAGUUAAUUCUUUUCAUUUAAUUACUCUGUAGUUAGAUAAUGUAGUCUGUACGUCAAUUCUUUGAAAUUAAUGAAGACUUCCUUUAAUGAAGACUUAAUACAAUCAAUUUUGAAAAUAUUCUAUAUUAAUUUGAAAAACAUGUAUAUUCUCUAUUUGUUAGGGGCAGUUAUCUAUCCAUUCACUGGCUUAUUUUGUUGUUUAAAUCUGCUAAUUGCUUAUUCAAUUUUGUGUGAUUUUUAUGUUUUUGCUAAAAAUGUGUUGAGAUCCCUCACUUAAGAUUAUGAAUUCGUCUCCUUUUUCCUUAUAAUUCUAUUUUGCUUUAUAUAUUUCAGAUCUAUAGCAUGAAGGUCAUACAAAUUCAUGAUUGCUACAUCUUUUUGGUGAAUUAUUCCAUCAGUUGUUAAUGACUAUGCCUCUGUAUCUUGGCGCAUUUUGCCUUCAGUUGUUUUUCUGUCCGACGGUAAUGUUGCUGCACCAUGUUUUCUUUCUCUAGUGCAGUAUUAGUGAGUUAUGCUUUAUAACAUUCCUUUAGUUUUGCACUUUCUGUGUGGCAGUUUUGUUUUAGGUGUGUCUUCUGUAGGUUAAAUAUAGCUGAAUUUUUCAAAAAAGCAAAUCUAAUAACCCAUGUUCAAUAGCUUUCUUUAAUCUAUUUGCAUUCUUUGUCUGAUUAUUGACACAUAGGGACUUAUUUGUAACAACUUUUUUUUUUUGAAGUUUUAAGUUUUAUUUAGGUUCCUUUUUCCCAUUCAGAUGGCAGCAUUCCAUACAUUCUGCUCUGUGCCUUGUCUUUUAAGAUAGUGGCAAAAUAUGCAUAACAUAAAAUUUACUGUUUUAAACUUUUAAAAUAUACAAUUCAGUGGCAUGAAAUAUAUUCACAGUGUUGCGCAACCACCAUCACUGAAUUUUUCCAGAACUUUUUCAUCAUCCCAAACAGAAAUUCUAUACCCAUCAAACUCUCCAUCAUCCCCUUUCCCCAAUCUCUGGUAACCCCUAUUUUACUUUCUUUCUUUUGACUAUUCUAAGUCCUUCACAUAAAUGGACUCAUACAAUAUCUGUCCCUUUGUAUCUGGCUUAGUUCACUUAGCAUAGUGUUUCUAAAGUGCCAUCCAUGUUGUAGCAUGUGUCAGAAUGUCCUCUCUUCUUAUGACUGCAUAAUAUUCCAUUGUAUGGAUGAAUCACGUUUUGUUUACCCUGAUGCUGCAAUGGACACUGAUGUAGCAGGUAUCUGGUUGAGUCCCUGCUUUCACUCCUUUUGCGUACAUACCCAGAAGUGGAAUUGCUGGAUCAUAUAGUAACUUUCUGAGGAACUGCCGUAUCUUUCCAUAGUGGCCAUACCAUUUUAUACCCCCACUAGGAAUAUACAAUACCAUCUUAUUUUGCAUUUUCUGAUUACUGCUUUUUCGCUUGCUUAUUUUUGCCUGAUUUAUGUUUUGGAAAAUUAGUGCUAAUGGCAAAGUGGAGGAAGUUGAAAGCGAGGUUAAUUAGGAGGCCACUGCAGCAGCACAGACCUGAACCCGGGCAGGGGUGGUGACAAUGAAGGAAAAAACACAGAUUCCAGAGACUUUUCCAACAUAUGCAUUGUAUCAUUUUUUCACUCAUUUAUUCAUUCAUUCCAUAAAUAUUUUUGAAUGCCCAUGAUCUCAGGAACAGGGAAGACAGAGUGAGCAAGAGAGUUACGGUCCCUGCCCUCCCAGCACUCACAGUCUAAAGUGACUAUUCCCAUAUGAAUCAUCAUGUAAUUAAAGGUCGGAGUGGAACCAUGGAAAAUGUGGCAAAGGAGCAGUAAUGGGCUGAGGGGGUGGGACGUGUUGAGCAAGCAUGGCAGUCGGGGAAGGCUUCCCUGAGGAGGUGUGUUUGGAUUAGGGGGAGUUCAUUGGGUGGAAGUAGAUUGAAGGUGGAUGCUAAGAGUGUUGUAGGCAGAGGAAACAGCAGGUGCAAAGGCCCUGUGGCAAGAGAGGGAGGGUGGAUGGUUCUAGGAACAGAAAGAAGACCAACACCACUACUAUAGUAUUGUUUAUAUUUCCAAGAUAUAUAAAACAUCUACAUGCUCAGUAUAAAGUGAAUUAUUAAAUAAAUCAAGGUGCUGCUAUAGUAUGGGGUAUGUACAGCAAUUAAAAUGGUAUGUAAAUCUAUUUACAUGGGAAACAUUCAUAACAUACUGAUGAGUAAUAAAAGAAAGAUGUUAUCUUUAUUACUUCUAUUGAUAAGUAAUAAAAGCACACUGAAGCAGUUUGUAGAAUAUGAUCUUAUUUUUGUUUACAUAUAAUCUGUAACCAAACAACAUAUACUUAUUUCAGUAUGUAUAGUUUUACAGAAAAAGUCUGAAAUAUAUUCAUCAAAUGAUCAUCUCUAGGGAAUGAGAUUCAGAUUGGAUGUAAUUUGUUUCUUUUUACUUAUUUGUAUUUUUAAAAAUUCCACAAUAAAUAUGAUUUACAUUUAUCAAAAAUAAAAUUAAUAAAAGACAUUUCUGAGCCAGAAUCAGUAGAUUUGGCAACCCUUGGAUGUGGGGAAACAGAGCAAGGUAAUUGUCAGAACCAACACAGGGGCUGUGUUACUGGGCAGAUGGUAACACCAUGGAUGGAGAGCAAGCACAGGAGGAGAGAGUGGCUGGAGCAGCACGAGGGGUGCAGAUGAAGACCGUGGGUGAAGGGGUGGACACGCUGAAUUGAAGAUAGAGAUUUCUGACUGGAAGCUGGGAUGUGGUUCUGGAACACAGUAGGGUCUAAAGCUCUCAAGAACAGUGAAGAGAGCCCUGGGUUUUCCAGGAGCUGGUUGAUUGCCUUUGAGAGUCUGUGGGCAGGAGGAGGAAAUCUGAACGCAAAGGUUAAAGAAUGAAUGGGAGAUGAGGAAUGAUAAGAGCACAUGUGGACAGCCCACCCUUUCAUUAUGUUUGGGAAAUAAAACAAUAAGGAUUUUAGGGUCUGGAGUGUGGGAGAGAGAGCAGGUUUGGUGAAAACAGAUUUUAAAAUCUUCAAAAGAUUAAAAGGGCAAGAGUUAAUAAAAUCAGUCAGCAAAAGAGUGUACGGUGAAAAAAAGAAGUGUGCCUAGCCUGGACCUCGGUGAGUAAACAUACUUUUACUGGGUAUGCAAUUCUAGGUUGUCAGGUUUUUUCUGCCAAUGCUUUGAAAACAGUCUGCUGUUUCCCAUUAUUUCUAACAAGCAGUCAGAUGCAAGUCUAGGUAAUGUAUCUUUCUACUCUAGUGCAUUUGAGAUUUUCUUUUUGUCUUUGGUUUUUCUUUUUGUUUGUCUUUCUUAGAGUUCAUUAGGUUUCCUAAAUCUGAGCAUCCACAGUUAUCAUCAGUUCCGGAAAACUCACAGAUAUCCUCACUCCAAAGAUGCCUCUCCCCCAUUUUCUCUCCUCUCUCCUUCCGUAAUGCUCACCAGACAGACACGUUAGCCUCUCUAACUCUUGACUGUUUCUCUUAACCUCUCUUGUAUAUUUGCAAUCUGUCUUCUGUGCUGCAUCUAGACUAAUUUCUUUAUCUUUUAUUCUGUCUUACUCUCAGUUUAUUAUUUUUAUCCAAAUCACAUACACAUAUAAUUUAGAGAGCCACAUAAUUGUACCAGGCUCAUGACAAAACAUAGUAGUACCCUGACAAUUGUUCCUUAUUUUCUGACCCCCAGGAACUUUCAACUCUUUUAACUGAAUCUUCUAAUAUUUGCUUCCAUAAGUCUAAAUAACAGGUCUGAAUUACUCCUCGGCUUUUCAGUUUGGUGUGAUCUAUUGUUUUUGUACUGUGGGAAAUGUGGAUUUAGCUUUAUUUCCUCUCCCACUCACACACCAACCCCUACCAACACACACAUUUCCCACACCCAGACAUGAGAUAGACUUGGUUAGAUUAGCAUUGAGUCUUUACAUUUUUAUGACGAUGAAAACUCUGGUCCCUGCUGAGCCUUCAUGAAUUAUCCUUUCCUGAACUUCUUUACCUUUCCCUUUCUGUUCAUACCCAGUACUUAGUCUUCUAUGCACACAACACUAACAUAACACUAACCUCUCCUCUGGUUGUGUAACGGUCUUCUCAACAUGCCCAGAAGUGGGGGCACUGUCAGUCCUGUCGUGAAGGCUUUUCCUGAGCUGCCUGGCCUGGCCUGCCAUGGAGGGGCUGGUUUCCAGGCCUGUGUGCAGCUCUCGUCUUGGACCCCCCUCUACUAUCAUGCUAAGGGGUUCACCAGCUUCUUUGUCAUGUUUGGGCUCCUGACUCCUGGAGCCCGCAUCUUCCUUGUGGGAUUCACAGCCUCAUUUUGGUGCAGUGCCUUCUCCAGUAGCUUCCAUGAGGAAGAGUACAUGGGAUGUAAUUUCUUCAGACCUUACGUGUCUAAAAAUGUCUUAGUCUAUCCUCAUGCUUAGAUGAUAAUUUAGAUUGGGAGUAUAACUUCAGGUUGGAAAUGGUUUUUCUUUGGACUUUUGAAGGCCUUACUGCAUUUCUUCUAGCUUCCAAUGUUGCUAGUGGAAUUUUAACAUCAUUGUUUUUCUUGAUCCUCUGUAUGAAAACUGUUUUAUACUUUCUAGAACCAUAGAGGAUCAUCUCUUAUUCCCAGUGCUGCAGAAUGUGCUCAUGCUGUCUUGGUUCCAGUCUCUUUCCUAGCUACUGUGCAGAGCCCAAGGCAGGUCCUUUCCCUUCAGAAACUCAUGGCCUUUAGUUCUGGGAAAUGUUCUGGAAUUAUUGUAUCCCCUUCAUUCUUAAUAUUCAGUAUUUCUGAAAUUCUUACUAUAUAAAUGUUGGAUUUUCUAGUCUGGCCCACUGUUGCUUUCUCCUCUGAUUAGUUCUAGUUUUCAUACCUUCUAGGUCUUUCAUCACUGUGAUUACUUUUUUGCUUCCUAAAAUAUCUUUUUUCAUAUCCUGAGAUUUUUAAUAAGAAUUAUUUUCCUGUUUCAUCGAUCAAUAACUUUUCUUAGUCUCUCUAAGGCUGUUGAUACCACUUUCCUCCUAGUUUUCUUUUCCAUGCAUGGUCCGUUUCUCUGGGCCCCUGUCUUUCAUACUCUGGAAGAUUUCCUAACAUGUCUGUGGAUC